AGGGACUCGCGGGAACCGCACCAAGCGGGUGGCUGCAGGAGCUCGCCCAUCGCCCCUGCGCUGCUCGGACCGCGGCCACAGCCGGACUGGCGGGUACGGCGGCGACAGACGGAUUGGCCGAGAGUCCCAGUCCGCAGAGUAGCCCCGGCCUCGAGGCGGUGGCGUCCGCGUCCUCUCGUCCAGGAGCCAGGACAGGUGUCGCGCGGCGGGCGCUCCAGGGACCGCGCUGAGGCCGCGGUCGCCGCCCGUCCCGCCCCGCCCCGCCGCCCGCCGCCCGCCGAGCCCAGCCUCCUUGCCGUCGGGGCGUCCCCAGGCCCUGGGUCGGCCGCGGAGCCGAUGCGCGCCCGCUGAGCGCCCCAGCUGAGCGCCCCCGGCCUGCCAUGACCGCGCUCCCCGGCCCGCUCUGGCUCCUGGGCCUGGCGCUAUGCGCGCUGGGCGGGGGCGGCCCCGGCCUGCGACCCCCGCCCGGCUGUCCCCAGCGACGUCUGGGCGCGCGCGAGCGCCGGGACGUGCAGCGCGAGAUCCUGGCGGUGCUCGGGCUGCCUGGGCGGCCCCGGCCCCGCGCGCCACCCGCCGCCUCCCGGCUGCCCGCGUCCGCGCCGCUCUUCAUGCUGGACCUGUACCACGCCAUGGCCGGCGACGACGACGAGGACGGCGCGCCCGCGGAGCGGCGCCUGGGCCGCGCCGACCUGGUCAUGAGCUUCGUUAACAUGGUGGAGCGAGACCGUGCCCUGGGCCACCAGGAGCCCCAUUGGAAGGAGUUCCGCUUUGACCUGACCCAGAUCCCGGCUGGGGAGGCGGUCACAGCUGCGGAGUUCCGGAUUUACAAGGUGCCCAGCAUCCACCUGCUCAACAGGACCCUCCACGUCAGCAUGUUCCAGGUGGUCCAGGAGCAGUCCAACAGGGAGUCUGACUUGUUCUUUUUGGAUCUUCAGACGCUCCGAGCUGGAGACGAGGGCUGGCUGGUGCUGGAUGUCACAGCAGCCAGUGACUGCUGGUUGCUGAAGCGUCACAAGGACCUGGGACUCCGCCUCUAUGUGGAGACUGAGGACGGAGAGACGUGGACUGGCUGGGGCUGGACCAAGGACUCCAGGCUUCAGAUGUGGAAACUGAGGCUCAGCAGGACCCCUUGGGUCCUCAGCCUCCACGCUCCUGGACCUGCCCAGGCCCCGGCAGAGAGACCGCUGCUGUGUCUGCUGCAGGGCCACUGCCCGGCCAGUCCGAGUCCCAUCCGCACCCCUCGGGCAGUGAGGCCACUGAGGAGGAGGCAGCCGAAGAAAAGCAACGAGCUGCCGCAGGCCAACCGACUCCCAGGGAUCUUUGAUGACGUCCACGGCUCCCACGGCCGGCAGGUCUGCCGUCGGCACGAGCUCUACGUCAGCUUCCAGGACCUCGGCUGGCUGGACUGGGUCAUCGCUCCCCAAGGCUACUCGGCCUAUUACUGUGAGGGGGAGUGCUCCUUCCCACUGGACUCCUGCAUGAAUGCCACCAACCACGCCAUCCUGCAGUCCCUGGUGCACCUGAUGAUGCCAGACGCAGUCCCCAAGGCGUGCUGUGCACCCACCAAGCUGAGCGCCACCUCUGUGCUCUACUAUGACAGCAGCAACAAUGUCAUCCUGCGCAAGCACCGCAACAUGGUGGUCAAGGCCUGCGGCUGCCACUGAGUCCACCCGCCCGGCCCAGCUGCAGCCACCCUUCUCAUCUGGAUCGGGCCCCUCAGAAGCAGGAAACCCUCAAACCCAGCCAGACCCCAGGCCGGGGCAUUGCCAGGGAGGACCCUCACAACCACGUACAUGACCCUUUCUCCUUCAUGCCAGGCUCCUAUGCUCCCCUUGCCCUGCCAGGCAUUUGUGUGACUGUCCUGUUUCCAGCCCAGGUGGUCUCAAUCAUCAGGCAGUGUUCUACCCAAAUGCAAACGCCUCUCCCGGAGGCAUGUCCUGGCUGGUUCUUUGGGGUUGGCACAGAAGUCCUGUCUGAGGUCCUAUCCAUGCCCCUUACUGGCUCAGGUCGUGAGAUAGAUGUGGAAUGACCUGAGAGGCACCUGGAGCCCACUGUUGGCCACCUUGAGCUCUUCACCAUCCAUCACAGGGUGUGGUGUGUGUAGUCAGGGUCUGGUUGGCUCCCCAUUGCCUGCCCGAGGUGCAAGGUGGGGUAUAAAACUGGAUAACCCCUGAAGUAUUGUAUAUUCAUGGAUCUGAAGCACUGAUCCACUGGUCACAGGUAGACAUGUGGAGUCAACUCAAGAAAAAGCUGAGUGAACAGCAUGAUUUAGGGCUAAAGCCAAUGGCAUUUAUCUUCCCUUGUCUUCCUGCUUUGCAUUUGCCUCUGCCAUCUAGGAAAGACAUGUAAGAGCAUGGACAUUUUACUUUGGAGAAACAGAAAAAUCUUGGGGCUUCCAAUUGACCCAUCUAUCUGCCACCAUGUUGCCCCACCAGGAGCUCAGCUCUGUGGAGUUUUCCCUUUGCUGAGCAAGCAUGUGGUUGCAUUGGGUGGCCCAGGAUGACAAUGCACAGCACAGAUGCCAUCAUUUCCCUUUCCCCUCUGAAUGGCAGACAUCAGUAAUCAAUCUGGAAUGUUUUUCUUCCAAAUCUGAGUGGAAUUUUCAAAUGAUCAGCACAGCCACUGCCAACAGAUAUGAUGUAAAGUGAAACCUGGUUGCCAUCUUCUGCCAUGCUGAGGAGCAGUCCAUCCCUGCCCGAGCAUGUAUCGGCAACAUGGGCAGCCUGUGACCGGGUCUGGGGCGAGGCCAGGGGCCAUCAAAAACAGGCUGAUCACCAAAGUCAGUGUCACCCUGGAUGCCCAGCAGCCCUGUCCUGUGUCUUGGGCCUGUGAGUCAAAGAAAAGGUCCUUUUCAGGGAGUGACAAGUAGUAAUUAGGCUGAGUUGGGUGGAGAGGUUUGUCUCAGCCUCUGCUGUUCUCGGAAACUGCUGUUCUCCUUGGAGCAGCCACUGGGAGUUGGAGUGUUUAUUUGAUUUCUGACUUGCUAAGCCUGUAAUUUACCUGCUGGAAUAGACAGAGUCCAGCUGCCCAAACCGUGUCAUUAAAAGCAGAUCCUGCGCCCGCCCCAUCCACAGGCACAGCCCGGCAGAGUGGUUCCACCUCCCCAUGGGCCCAAGGAUGCGCCUCUCUGGAGUUCACGUGCUGCACCCCCAGGGAGGGGCCUGGGGAAAGCUGGUCCAGCAGCAGGGGUGGAGGCUGGGGCCACACUGCGGGACAGCAGCCCCUCCACCUGGACCAGGGAGGGCCUCCAUGUGCAAGCGCAGAGGAAGAGACCCUCCCAUGUACGCAAAGGGCAGCCCCAGGCUGUCUGGAAGUUGGAGAAUUCCCUAUCAGCACAGGGAUCUCAGCUCUGGCCUGGAGGUGAAGAGACCUGCCUUGUAGGUGGCUUCCUUAUCUGCGCCUCCAUUUUCUAUCUGCACUUUUUGAUCUCCAAACAACCUUCAGCCAAAGAAUCUGUCUACCAACUCCUCAUAGUGAGCCAGAAGCAGCCUCAUAACCCUGAAUGUGGGGCUCUGGUGGCUGUCACGAAGCAGAGUUGGCACAUAACAUGGAACCUGGCCAGGCAUGGUGGCUCACACCUAUAACCCCAGCACUUUGGGAGGCCAAGGCAGGCAGAUCACCUGAAGUCAGGAGUUCAAGACCAUCCUGGCCAACACAGUGAAACCCCAUCUGUACUAAAAAUACAAGAUUACCUGGGCAUGGUGGUGCAUGCCUAUAAUCCCAGCUACUCAGGAGGCUGAGGCAGAAUUGCUUGAACCUGGGAGGUGGAGGUUGCAGUGAGCAGAGAUCACAACAUUGCACUUCAGCCUGGUGACAUGAGCAAAACUGUUGUCUCAACAAAAUGAAAUUAUGGAACCUGUUUGCCAUCCUAGUAUUUACUUAAUUGUUCCUUCUUAACAUCAAAGAUGGUCUUCUAGGCAAUUGUAAAUUUUAAAUUAGCCAGUUAUUUUGACAAUUAAUUUUUUACUCCACCUGUAUCUUUAGUGCCCAGCCAAUGAUCUGGCAUAGUUAGGGGUGCACCAAGAAUGUCUGUAAACUACCUGAAGGUUUGUAGAUAUGGAGUACACCUUACCCAUUAAUCAAGCUGUGCAUAGCAGGAACCAAUACGAGCCGUGAUCCUCCUGGUUCAUACAGAACAAUGGAAAAACAUAAGGCUUUGUCUACCUAGUUGGCCAUCAGACUUUCAGCAACUUUUAUCAUCCAGAUAGUCACCAAAUGAAAUAAAAUAGAAAAAUCCCUUGAGCAAUGAAACAAUUGUGAAUGAACACAAAGUCCAUGAAUUUAAUCCUUAUCCGUUUGCUGAGCCAAGCAUGUGCAUCUGCAGUGGGUGGCCCAGGCUGGCAGCACAGAUACCACCAUUUCCCUUUUCUUUGCUCAGGGCAUGGCCUGUUUAUCUCGUUGCACCAGAUGAGGGUUGGAAGGAUGAUGGUGGUGGUUGUUUCAGAUCUACUGACAGCAAUGAGAAAUCAAUGACAGUUGACAGGAAGAGAGGACGCAUACAACAGGCAAAAGAGGAAUGCCCAGCAGUCUUGGUCCUUGCGGUGCAAUACUGGCCUUGAGGCCAAGUCAGCAGGGGAUUCGUAGUCACUAACUUCUAACUGAGGCAGGGAAGUAACAUGUUCUGGAAAAGGUCCAAAGAAACAGGAAUAGAGGCAGUGUAGCAAGAGGCAGAUUUUUGGUGCCAAAUAGAUUUGAAUCCUGGUUCUGCUUCUUCCUUUGUAGAGUAUGAUAUUGGUUCUUUCCUCCCAAAGCUAUUAUAAAGACUAAAUAUGUACACAAAUCUUUGGGAUGUCUGACAUAUAAAUGCUUAACAAUAGGUAUUUGCUGGUAUUAUUACAAAUGAAUUUGCUUAUUUUUGAGCCACUUCUAUGUCUGUCCAUUAAACCAAAAUGUGUUCUGCA